GGGCCGGGAGGGCCGCGGCCACCGGAAGAGUCGCGGUCGCCAGUCCAGUCGGGAGAGUGGGGAGCGGAAGCGGCGGCCGCGGCGGCGGCGGGCGGCGCUGGGACCCGGUAGCGGCCGGAGAACAAGGGAGCUGGCGCCGCCAGCAGCCGCCGAGCUGGGUUGAGCCGCUGGGCCGCGCCGCGCGCCGCCGCCGUCUGGGAGGCUCGGCCCGGCCGCCCGAGCAGGCCGCGCGCGGGCCGCCGGGCCCGAGGCCAGAGCCAUGGGCGAGACCAAGAUCAUCUACCACUUGGAUGGGCAGGAGACGCCGUACCUUGUGAAGCUGCCCCUGCCCGCCGAGCGCGUCACCUUGGCGGACUUUAAGGGCGUUUUGCAGCGACCCAGCUAUAAGUUCUUCUUCAAGUCUAUGGACGACGAUUUCGGAGUGGUGAAGGAGGAGAUCUCGGAUGACAAUGCCAAGCUACCAUGCUUCAAUGGCCGGGUGGUGUCCUGGCUGGUGUCAGCUGAGGGCUCACACCCAGACCCAGCCCCCUUCUGUGCUGAUAACCCAUCGGAGCUGCCACCACCUAUGGAGCGCACGGGAGGCAUCGGGGACUCCCGACCCCCAUCCUUCCACCCUCAUGCUGGUGGGGGCAGCCAGGAGAACCUGGACAAUGACACAGAGACGGACUCUUUGGUGUCUGCCCAGCGAGAGCGGCCACGCCGGAGGGAUGGCCCAGAGCAUGCAACCCGGCUAAAUGGAACUGCGAAGGGGGAACGGCGGCGAGAACCAGGGGGUUAUGAUAGCUCAUCCACCCUUAUGAGCAGUGAGCUGGAGACCACCAGCUUCUUUGACUCAGAUGAGGAUGACUCCACCAGCAGGUUCAGCAGCUCCACAGAACAGAGCAGUGCCUCACGCCUGAUGAGAAGACACAAGCGGCGGCGGCGGAAGCAGAAGGUUUCUCGGAUUGAGCGGUCCUCGUCCUUCAGCAGCAUCACGGACUCCACCAUGUCACUCAACAUCAUCACGGUCACUCUCAACAUGGAAAAAUAUAACUUCUUGGGCAUCUCCAUUGUGGGCCAAAGCAACGAGCGUGGUGACGGCGGCAUCUACAUUGGCUCUAUCAUGAAGGGUGGGGCCGUGGCUGCUGAUGGACGCAUCGAGCCAGGAGAUAUGUUGUUACAGGUAAACGAGAUCAACUUUGAGAACAUGAGUAAUGACGAUGCAGUCCGGGUACUGCGGGAGAUUGUGCACAAACCGGGGCCCAUCACCCUGACUGUAGCCAAGUGCUGGGACCCAAGUCCACGUGGUUGCUUCACAUUGCCCAGGAGCGAGCCCAUCCGGCCCAUUGACCCUGCGGCCUGGGUCUCCCACACUGCAGCCAUGACCGGCACCUUCCCUGCAUACGGCAUGAGCCCCUCCCUGAGCACCAUCACCUCCACCAGCUCCUCCAUCACCAGUUCCAUCCCUGACACAGAGCGCCUAGACGACUUCCACUUGUCCAUCCACAGUGACAUGGCUGCCAUCGUAAAAGCCAUGGCCUCCCCUGAAUCAGGGUUGGAGGUCCGUGACCGCAUGUGGCUCAAGAUUACCAUCCCUAAUGCUUUCAUCGGCUCAGAUGUGGUGGACUGGCUGUACCACAAUGUGGAAGGCUUCACGGACCGGAGGGAGGCCCGCAAGUAUGCCAGCAACCUGCUGAAAGCUGGCUUCAUCCGCCAUACCGUCAACAAGAUCACCUUCUCCGAGCAGUGCUACUACAUCUUCGGUGACCUCUGCGGCAACAUGGCCAACCUGUCUCUCCACGAUCACGAUGGCUCCAGUGGCGCCUCUGACCAGGACACACUGGCCCCUUUGCCGCACCCGGGGGCCGCCCCUUGGCCCAUGGCUUUCCCGUACCAGUACCCGCCACCCCCGCACCCAUACAACCCGCACCCGGGCUUCCCGGAGCUGGGCUACAGCUACGGCGGGGGCAGCGCCAGCAGUCAGCACAGCGAAGGCAGUCGGAGCAGUGGCUCCAACCGUAGCGGCAGCGAUCGGAGGAAGGAGAAGGACCCGAAGGCCGGGGACUCCAAGUCCGGGGGCAGCGGCAGCGAAUCGGACCACACCACACGCAGCAGCCUGCGGGGGCCGCGGGAGCGGGCGCCCAGCGAGCGCUCAGGGCCGGCGGCCAGCGAGCACAGCCACCGCAGCCACCAUUCCCUGGCCAGCAGCCUUCGCAGCCACCACACACACCCGAGCUACGGUCCUCCCGGAGUGCCCCCUCUCUACGGCCCCCCCAUGCUGAUGAUGCCCCCGCCGCCCGCGGCCAUGGGGCCCCCAGGAGCCCCUCCGGGCCGCGACCUGGCCUCAGUGCCCCCGGAACUGACCGCCAGCAGACAGUCCUUCCGCAUGGCCAUGGGAAACCCCAGUGAGUUCUUUGUGGAUGUGAUGUGAGCAGGGCCCCUCCCCCAGCUCCAUUCCGCUCCCACCCCAGCCGGCUGCGUUCCUCUCUCCAUCCGUCCGUCUUUUUUACUUUGUCUGGUACCUGAAAGGGAAAUAAAAGGAACUAAAUCCAGGUGCGCUAACUGCUCGCAGGGUGCUGCGAGGGUGGGGUGCACCUACCGAUUGGCUCUGCAGCCCCCUAACCUGCCUCUGGCCCCAGUUCGUUUCCUCUGCCCACUAAUCCCUGCGCAGGACUUCCCAGGACCCCUUUUGUCUCUGGGACCAGACUUGUUGGUGCUACCCCUUACUCCCCUCUGCAACCCCCAUUUUGGGAGUUGACCCCAGCAAUGACCUUGGUGGCACGCUCACUCCCUCAUUCUCUCGUUUCCCCUUUAGCUCCCUUUCACCAUUUAUUCAGCUACAUCAUCCCUCUAUUAACCCCACCCCAUCAGGCACGUGUGCAAACCUCUUGACUUUACCCCACAUUACUGAAACCAAAAUAUAUUUGCUUCAUCUGCCCCUACUAACCAUCCCCCUGCCUGCUGCCUCAGUCCUGCAACCUAAAGCUGUAGUCGCCUCCAAUAGCCAUCCAUGCCAUCCCUGCCUGUGCCUAGAUCAGAGGCCCAGAGGGCCCCCUCAGUUGCCUGAGCAGCUGGUGGCUUCCAGGGAGCAUCUCUGCUCUACCCCUGCCCCAUGCCUGCCCUGCGUGCUGGUUCCUUCAGACCCCUAACCCUACUAACCAGCAGGCUCAUCUCACCUCCAGGCCUGAAACAUUUCUUUUCUUUCUUUUUUCCUCCCCCAAUUUACCCUGGGCCUGGAGCAGCCAAGAAUUUCGGGCUGUUUGACUUUCUGUGAGCCCCCAGCGAGGGGAGGCCCAGCCUCCGAGGAGACCAGGAACCCUGCUUCAGCAGCCCCUCAGGGCUUCCCAAGGAUGUCCAGCCCCCACACCCACACGUUAACAUAAUGAGUCACUAGGCUUCUGGGGAGGGCCCAACUUCACCCAUGCAUGAGAGACUCUCCUCCUUUCCAGAGAGAAUCGGAUCGCACCACGUGUGGCAGCCUGCGGCGGGGGGAGGGGGGCCUCUUUAGCUCUCUUUAUCUUUCUCUCUCACUCAUGUAUGCAUACAUGCACAGAGAUGCAUACACAGGUGCCUAUGCAAGUUCAUUUAAGCCUCAGGGCUGGUCCCUGCCCAAAGGGCUGGACCCUCCUAAUCCUCUCCUAGGUUGUGGGGCUGGUCCCCUGACACCCUUCUCCCCUUCCUGGUAGACCUUAAACCUCGCACACAUGUCCCCAGCAUUUUCUCACCUGGAUAAAGCCCAUAAGCUGGGUCUCAGGCUGGGCUCAGCAAAGGACUCGCCUUGCAACCGACAGGCCAUUCCCACCCCCACACACAACCUCCCCUGUUUUCACAUUCACCAUGGCAUCCCAGAGCAAGGACACAGGAGCCCACAGGCCAGUUGAGGUUGGGCAAGGAGACUUCCAGGACUUCCAGACAGAGUACCAGGUUUUAUUUUUCACCUUAUUCUCUACUUUAAACAAAUCAUAACUUUCUCUUUAAGCCUCUGCUAUAAAUUCUCCUGGCUCUCCUGGGCUUCCAUAUUUUGGGGGCUGGGGUGUCAAAAGUGAGAUGAAGUUCUUAGCUCCAGGUUUUGGGGUAAACCAAGGUAGGAACAUUUUGGCAUUUAUUUCAAUUAACAAUACUUCCUUGGACGGGUGCGGUGGCUCACGUCUGUAAUCCCAGCACUUUGGGAGGCUGAGACAGGUGGAUCACUUGAGGUCGGGAGUUCGAGACCAGCCUGGCCAACAUAGCAAAACCCUGUCUCUACUAAAAAUACAAAAAUUAGAUGGGUGUUUUGGCACCUGCCUGUAAUCUCAGCUACUCAGGAGGCUGAGGCACAAGAAUCGCUUGAAUCCAGGAAGCAAGCGGAGGUUGCAGUGAGUUGAGAUCGCACUCCAGCCUGGGUGACAGAGUGAGAUUCUGUCUCAAAAGCAAACUAACAAAGAAAAACAAUACUUCCUGGGGUUUUGGUGUGCAGAGGGCUUUGUUGGAAGUGUGACUCAAUCUUGCCUGCCUUCUGGGAGCUCUAGAAUUGUUCCCAACCCAGUCCAUGGCUUCUAGCCACCACUACAGGGCUGUUUCAUGUACUUCUCUCUCUGACUCUGUCUUGUCCGACUCUCUUGAGAAUUUCUCAACGAUUGCUCAUGCCUGUCAGUAUCAGUGCUUCCAUCGUUCCAUCUUUGAUUCACUUCUCUUUCCUUUCUAUUUACUCCCAAAAUGGAGUCAUUCAUCCUGAUGUCCUCAAUUGCUGCUGAUAUGCUGGUGAUUCCCAAAUACAUAGCUCCAACCCCCAACUUCCCCCAGACUUUAGAUCUGUAUUGGUAUUACCUACUGGACAUCUCUAUGGACAGUUCCGUAUAGACUCAACUCAUCUGCCCAACCAAGUAUGUUCCUCCUGAAUUCCUCUCCUGGUUACUUCAUCACAAUCUACAUAGGCUCACCAGCUAGAAACAUUUAUGAGCUUACAUUCCUUCUUCCCAUAUCUUAUCAGCAUAUCAUAUCCAUUUCACUCCAACACUCUGUCUUGAAUUUGGCCCUCCCUCUCCCCUCUCUACUUUAAUUCAUUGGAGCAUGGGAUUUGGAGUUAGGUGGUUUUGGGUUUGAAUUCCAGCUCUACUAUUUUUGGUUGUGUGAUAGAGUUAUUUAACCUCUCUGAGCCUCAGUUCCCUCGUAUGUAAAAUGAUGAUAAUAAUACCUACCUCACAGGGUUGUUGUGAGGAUUUAAAUUAGAUAUUGUACGAAAAGUGCCUAGCACAGUGCCUGGCACACAGUAGAGUAGGUGCUCAAUAAAUGGUAGCUAUUAUUAUUAUUA